GUUAACUUCCUGACCCAGGAAGUGGCAGCAACAGAGGGGACUAGCAGCGAAUAUACUUUACACCAAAUCUCAGAAGAUUCAGAACUUAGAUGAGUGGGGCCCAGGACAGGAACCCUGGAGCCUUGGAAGGAGGGGAGCCCCAUCUCCCCAGAAGAGCAGUGACCCCAGCAGAGAGGGGCCUGGUGUAUCACUGGAGGAAAUAGCCUGCCAAGGAAUACACGUCUUCAGAAGAAAUUCUGUGUGGCUUCAAGAGACUGAUCAAAUUGUGAGAGGAAAACAGCCUACCCGGUCCUCUUUUCUUCAAUACAAAAUGAGAUAAUAGGGGUUGGAAGGAAAACCUUCAAGACCUAUGGAAGUCAGUUGCAGCCAGCUCAUCACAUAGAGGUGCAGGUGAGGUGUAUUUUCAUCACGGUGGAAAAUUCUGGCUGCUUCAUCUCCAUCUCUAGAGCCAAUAUUGGAGCUUUUCAAUAAAAGCUAUGGCCUCAACCACCAGCACCAAGAAGAUGAUGGAGGAAGCCACCUGCUCCAUCUGCCUGAGCCUGAUGACGAACCCAGUAAGCAUCAACUGUGGACACAGCUACUGCCACUUGUGUAUAACAGACUUCUUUAAAAACCCAAGCCAAAAGCAACUGAGGCAGGAGACAUUCUGCUGUCCCCAGUGUCGGGCUCCAUUUCAUAUGGAUAGCCUCCGACCCAACAAGCAGCUGGGAAGCCUCAUUGAAGCCCUCAAAGAGACGGAUCAAGAAAUGUCAUGUGAGGAACACGGAGAGCAGUUCCACCUGUUCUGCGAAGACGAGGGGCAGCUCAUCUGCUGGCGCUGUGAGCGGGCACCACAGCACAAAGGGCACACCACAGCUCUUGUUGAAGACGUAUGCCAGGGCUACAAGGAAAAGCUCCAGAAAGCUGUGACAAAACUGAAGCAACUUGAAGACAGAUGUACGGAGCAGAAGCUGUCCACAGCAAUGCGAAUAACUAAAUGGAAAGAGAAGGUACAGAUUCAGAGACAAAAAAUCCGGUCUGACUUUAAGAAUCUCCAGUGUUUCCUACAUGAGGAAGAGAAGUCUUAUCUCUGGAGGCUGGAGAAAGAAGAACAACAGACUCUGAGUAGACUGAGGGACUAUGAGGCUGGUCUGGGGCUGAAGAGCAAUGAACUCAAGAGCCACAUCCUGGAACUGGAGGAAAAAUGUCAGGGCUCAGCCCAGAAAUUGCUGCAGAAUGUGAAUGACACUUUGAGCAGGAGUUGGGCUGUGAAGCUGGAAACAUCAGAGGCUGUCUCCUUGGAACUUCAUACUAUGUGCAAUGUUUCCAAGCUUUACUUCGAUGUGAAGAAAAUGUUAAGGAGUCAUCAAGUUAGUGUGACUCUGGAUCCAGAUACAGCUCAUCACGAACUAAUUCUCUCUGAGGAUCGGAGACAAGUGACUCGUGGAUACACCCAGGAGAAUCAGGACACAUCUUCCAGGAGAUUUACUGCCUUCCCCUGUGUCUUGGGUUGUGAAGGCUUCACCUCAGGAAGACGUUACUUUGAAGUGGAUGUUGGCGAAGGAACCGGAUGGGAUUUAGGAGUUUGUAUGGAAAAUGUGCAGAGGGGCACUGGCAUGAAGCAAGAGCCUCAGUCUGGAUUCUGGACCCUCAGGCUGUGCAAAAAGAAAGGCUAUGUAGCACUUACUUCUCCCCCAACUUCCCUUCAUCUGCAUGAGCAGCCCCUGCUUGUGGGAAUUUUUCUGGACUAUGAGGCCGGAGUUGUAUCCUUUUAUAACGGGAAUACUGGCUGCCACAUCUUUACUUUCCCGAAGGCUUCCUUCUCUGAUACUCUCCGGCCCUAUUUCCAGGUUUAUCAAUAUUCUCCUUUGUUUCUGCCUCCCCCAGGUGACUAAGGAAAAGAGCAGAAGCUCCUUGGUUUAACCAGCACAGAGAAAAUAAUAUAAAUCCCAUAAGGGCAGACGUUUGGUCUGUUUUCUUCGCUGUCAUUUCCUUAGUAGUUAGACUAGUGCUGAGAUUUUAGUGGAUAUAUAAUUGAUUUAUGUUGAAUAUAUGGACUUAGCAACUAAAAAUACCACAGAUGGUUAACCUGGACUGGGGCAAAGCAAGAUAAUAGUGAUGAUCGUAUGUUGCUGUCUCCAUCCGUCUUUAAUGGGUCAGGGCUUUGAUUUCCAAGGGUCUUCAGGUGAUGAGUAGGGGUACCCACAAGUCAGAAGGUCUGCGUUCUCCUAGUUUGUUUGCUGCCAUUUGAACUCAUGUAGGGAAUGAAAGAAAGCUGCAAUUAUCCGCCAACUGCAUUUAAAACAAAACAAAACAGAAAAAUCAAAAUAACAUUGACUCUUCCAACCACUGACAUGUUGUUUAAUAAUCUAAGCGGCAGUCCUGGAGGCUACCAGACUUACUGAGUUCUACCUGAGAAACAGCCAAGCAAAGUGUGAGAGAAGGGUUAAGACUGGCUUACAAUGAGAUGCUUCAAAUGAAAAGGGAAUUAUGAGUAAAAUUGAACUUUGAUGGGGGAUUCAGUUCUGGAAAAGAAUUUGGUAUUUUCCAGUCUGCUAGGACCAAUUACCUUGAAAUAUUUUAAAAUCUCAGUAAAUAGUUAUUGCUGAAAUGGCUGUUGGCAGUUCUUAUUAUGAUUCAGAGAAGAGCAAAUAGACCUUAACUUCAUUUUGAAAAAGACCAAAUUACCAUACCCGAGUGAGUAAUGACAGGACUACAACUAAAACAUAAACAACAUUAAUGAUGACCAUAAAAAGUCACAAAAUUGCUAAAUGUUAUAAUUUAGAGUUGACAUAAAAAUUGAUGGCCAGGCAUGGUGGCUCACGCCUGUAAUCCCAGAACUAUGUGAGGCUGAGGCAGGUGGAUCACUUGAGGUCAGGAGUUCAACACCAGCCUGGCCAACAUGGUGAAACCCUGUCUCUACUAAAAAUACAAAAAUUAGCCGGGCAUGGUGGUAGGGGCCUGUAACCCAGCUACUCGUGAGGCCAAGGCAGGAGAAUUGCUUGAGCCUGCAGCAGCUGCAGUAAGCCAAGAUCAUGCUGUGCCUCAAGGAAAAAAAAAAUUAAUGUUUACUGAUAUUUGUUGAAGUCCUACAACAUCACCUCUGAGAAUAGGAGAAAUGAAGCAACAGUUGUGUCUAGAUGUCAGAGGCAUGGCUGGGCCUCCAUCUCUGCCUAAGGGAGAUAUAAAAGAGUUCAAACUAUUGCCCAUGUUCCCCAGGGUCAGAAGUUCUAAUUAUGAUGAUAGAGGCUGGGUUGUAAGUAGUAAGUGAAGGGUAGCAGAAUAUGCCAUCUUUGGCAUAAGAAGUAUUUUGAGUUGAAGACAAUUGAGAAAAAAAAUAGAUUAAAAACAAACAAACACCUCUGCCCUCUCCCUAUUUGCCUAAAAGCAGGAUAUGAAAUUGUGAAGGUGUCUUCUUACUCGGGGAAGAACAAAAGUUAGUCACCAGAGACUUUAGACUCUUAUCAGCCUGGACAUAGCACCAGAGAAGUCUUUUUUUUUAAAAAAAAAAAAAAAAAAAGGGAAAGAAAAAGUUGCCUUCCCACAAUUUACUGCACUAGAAACUCAAAGUCCUUUUCGUCUUCCUUGUCACUUAAAAAAUGUAUUCUUUUCUUAAAAUGCUAUAUAAGCCCAAGUUCUAAAUCCUCUUUUGAGUAUUCAUCUCAGUACUCCCCUGUGUUUGUACAAUGCACAUGCUUUGUUUCUGUCUUGUCAAUCUGUCUUUUGUUAGUCUACUUGAUAGGGCCACAGAUGGAGAACCUAAGAUGAAUAGAAAAAAAAGAUUUUUCUCCCCAACAGAAGGAUUAUCGCCAGUUGCACUUGUUCUAUAUACCCGUAGUCUCGGUAUGCUGACCCAGACUUGGGUAAUAGGACCCAGUGGGUAACCGAGGAACCCCACCUUUGUGCAGGAUCAGUGAAGAUGUAAUCUGGAUAUUCAUAAGCUCUUCUCUACCUCUUGGCAUCCCACAGUCCUGUGUUAAUGUAAGUGUGGUCUUCCCCAGAAAGGGGAGGCCUCCCUAACAUUGUUAAAGCCUAGCAUAUGCUGCUUAGAGGAAAUUCUAUAUCCCUAAGCACUUAGAUUGCUGAAUAAGAAAGAAUGAUAAUAAAAUAAACAAUUAAAUAAAAGUUUUAAAAAAUGAAUAAAAUAAACCUGUGGAAACUAUAAGGAAGGCCAGAAGAAAUAUAAAAUUGGAGAUUAAUUGGGGUGCAGGAAAGUUAUGGAAAGAAUAUAAGUCCUGCUAGAUAAAUCAUUAGCUAUUUUAAUAAAGAAUACAGAAGAAAAUAGGAACAAAAGAAUAUAUACUGGAAUAAUUUUGAGAGUAAUUUGAAGAAUUAGAUGCAAAUAAAUUUGAAAACCUUUAAAAAGAAACCAAUGGCCUAACUGACCCAAGAAGGGAAAGAAAAUCUAAACAGACUGAUAAAUACAAAAUGAAAUUCAGACACUUACAGAGCAGCCAGGCAUGGUGGCUCACACCUGUAAUCCUGUCACUUUGGGAGGCUGAGAUGGGAGGAUCACUUGAGGCUAGGAGUUUGAGACUAGCCUGGGCAAGGCUCCCAUCUCUAAAAGAAAAGAAAUUAGCUGGGCAUGGUGGCAUGUGCCUUAGUUUCAGCUACUCAGGAGGCUGAGACGAGGAUUGCUUGAGCCUAGGAGGGCAAGGCUGCAGUGAGCCAUGGUCAUGCCACUGAAUUCCAGCCUAAGUGACAGAGCAAGACCUUGUCUCAAAAAAAAAAAAAAAAAAAGUUACAGAGCUCCAACUAAAUAAUGUGGGGAACAAAAGAAAAAAGAAGAUGAUUUUAUGGCUGAUUUUUUUUUUAAGGAAAAGCAAUUCAUGUACCCUUGAAGAUUAGAUUAAGUUCUAUAAAAUAGCCCAAAAUGACAGUGGCUGAAACAAGUUUAUUUCUCUCCCAUUUAAAGCAAGUCUAGAUGUGGAAGUCUGGGAAGCCCAGAAAAUCCAGGUCUUGUUUGUGUAUGGAAACUCCAGAAAAUCACAGAUUCCUUCCAGCCACCCCUCAAUUACCCCUGGGAUCCAAGAGAGCCACUAAAGUUCCAGCCAUCAUACUCACAACCCAAGUUGUAGGAUGGAAAAAAGGACACAAAAGUAGGGUGAAGAGCAUGUGUGCAACAGCUCUCUUUUACUCUAGUGUCCUAAAACCUAUCAUAAAACCUUUGGCUUGCCUUGCAUUAGCCAGAAUUUAGUACAUGGCCACACUUAAGAAGUCAGAAAGAUUAGCUUUUUUUCCAGGGUAGUUGGCUGAAAAUCAGGAGUUCUCAUAUUAAAAAACAGAGAAGGGACAUCGAAUAGAUGACCAACAAUCUCCUUCACACUCAUACUAUUUAAACUGUCCUAGUCAAUGACCAAAAAAGAAAAGCCUACAAACUCAUUGAUAUAAAAGCUUAACAAAGGUACUCCCCGCCCCCCGCCCGCCACACACCAUCCCCAAAAGGAAAUUUCUAAUCCAAUUAACAGUCUUAGGUUGGGCUGCUGAAACAAAAUACCACAGCCUGAGUGACUUAAACAACGACAAUUUAUCUCUCACUGUUCUGAGGUCUGAGUUGAUUCUUUGUGAAGGCCCUUUCCUAGCUUGCAGAUGGCUACCUUCCUGCUAUGUCUUCACAUGGCAAAGAGAGAGCUAGCUUUCUGGUCUUUUCUUAUAAGGGACCAGUCCCAUCAUGCCCAUCAUGAAGACUCGAUCUGCUAGGAUCUCAACUAAACCUAACUAUCACCCAAAGAGCCCACCUCCAAAGACCAUCACAUUGAAUGUGAGAGUUUCUACAUAUGCAUUGUGGGAAACACAAACAUUUACUUCAACUGUAACUAUUGAAGCAAAAAUGUCCCCCCACCAUAGACAUCCAGCACCACAGUAGUACAUUUAUUACAAUUGAACUUACAUUGACACGUCAUUAUCAACGAAAGUCUGUAAUUUACAUUAGGGUUUAUUCUUGGUGUUGUGCUUUCUAUGGGUUUUGACAAAUGUAUAAUGUCAUGUAUUCACCAUUAUAGUAUCACAGAAGUUUCACUGCCCUAAAAAUCCUGUGUUCUGCCUUUUCAACACUUCCUGUCACCCAAUUUCUAUCAACUAAUCUUUUGACUGUGUCCAUAGUUACUGUCUUUUCUAGAGUGUCAUACAGUUGUGAAGCAGGAAGCAGGAGUGAACUCCGGAGGCAGGGACUUUACUCCGGACCAGAUUGAAGACUAGCCGAAACAGGGACGAGGUUAAAGCACCUCUCCAUAAGACACGCCCACCAGCGCCAUGUCAGUUUUUCGUUGCCAUGGCAACAACAGGACAUUAUCGACUUCUUUCCUCUGUACCUACUCCGAAGUUACCACUCUUUUUCUAGAAAUUUCUGCAUAAUCCCCCUUAACAUGCACUUAACUAAAAGCAGGUAUAUUACUGCAGAACUGCCCCUGAGCUGCUACUCUGGGCACAUUACUUAUGGGUUAGCCCUGCUCAGCAAGGAGCAGUACCUGUUCUGCUGUUGUACACUGCUGCUUCAGUAAAAGUUGCUAACACCACCACUUCACCCUUGAAUUCUUCCCGGGCUAAGCCCUAAUUUUUGGCUUGCUUGCCCUGCAUCAGUUGGAGUCAUAUAGUAUGCAGUCUUUUCAGGUUGGCUUUUUAGUAACAUACAUUUAAGUUUCCUUCAUGUGUUUUCAUGGCUUGAUCGUUUCUUUUCUUUUUCUUUUUCUUUUUUCUUUUCUUUCUUUUUUUUUUUUUUUUUGAGACAGAGGAGUCUUGCUCUGUUGCCCAGGCUGAAGUGCAGUGGCACUGGCUCACUGCAACCUCCAUCUCCCAGGUUCAAACGAUUCUCAUAUCUCAGCCUCCCGAGUAGCUGGGAUUACAGGCUCACGCCACUAUGCCCGGCUAAUUGGGGUUUUCCCAUGUUGACCAGGCUGGUCUCAAACUCCUGGCCUCAAGCAAUCCACCCACUUCGGCCUCCCAAAGUGAAUGCAUUUCUUUUUAACUCUAAAUAACAUUCCAUUAUUCAGAAGUACCACAGUUAUCCACUUACCUACUGAAAGACAUCUUGUUUCCAAGUUUUGGAUAAAUUAUGAAUAAAGCUGCUAUAAACAUCUAUGUGCAGGUUUUUGUGUGGAGAUAAGUUUUCAAUUCCUUUGGAUAAAUACUAAGGAGUGUGAUUGGUGAAUCUUAUGGUAAAAGUAUGGUUACUUUUGUAAGAAACCACCAAACUGUCUUCCAAAGUGAUUGCACAUUUUGCAUUCUCACCAGUAAUGAACAAGUUACUAUUGCUACAUAUCUUUGCAACCUUUGGUGCUGACAGUGUUCUAAAUUUUGGUCAUUCUACUAGGUAUGCAGUGGUAUCUACUUGUUUUAAUUUGCAGUUCCCUAAUGACAUGAUGUCAAGCAUCUUUUCAUAUGCAUACUUGCAUCUGUGUAUCUUCUUUGGUGAACAGAUGUUCAGGUCAUUGGCCUGCUUUAAAUCAGGUUAUUUUCUUACUGUUGAGUUUUAAGUAUUCUUUGUAUAUUCUAAAAAUAUUGUUCUUCAUCAGAUCUGUCUUUUGCAAACAUUACCUGCCAAUGUGUGGCUUUUCUUCAACACUUCUUUGUAAAUUUGCAAGUCCUUUGAGAAAAGAAAUGCACCCAAAGUAUUAAUUUGGCAAUCUCAUAUCACGAGAGUACUCUAAAGCUAAAUAAAUUACAGUUUUUCAAAUUUUGAAUUAAUUGAUCUUUGCUAUUGUUAGCAAGGUCUUGUAUUCUUUUUUUUUUUUUUUUUUUUUUUUAAUAGAGACGGGUCUUGCUACAGUGCCCAGGCUGGUCUCGAACUCCAGGCCUAAAAUGAUCCUCCUGCCUUGGCCUUCCAAAGUACUGGGAUUACAGGCAUAAGUCACCACGCUCAGCCAUCUGGUAUUCUUUAGCAACUGUUUGGUAACUUAAUCUUUCACUUUUUGAAAACAAAAAAUAGUUUUUUUCUCAUAGUUUUCUAACAAAAUCUUCAUAACUGAAAUAAUUUCUCUUUAUCACCUCUUCUUAUAAAUAUGGUUUUCUUUUUUUAAAUAAAAAUUUAAGACAUUUUAUAACUGGCCAAAUUUACUAGCUUAGAUACUAUUAGAUAGUCAAUAUUUUUUGUUGGAUAUUUGAUUUUUAUUUCAGGCAACUAAUAUCUAUUCAUUUUUGCACUGUUGGAAGAAAAUUACUGAUCAAAUUCACUAUGUAUUUGCAGAAAAUGGCUUUCAAUAUUGUCUACUUUAUCAUCCUUUUUUUUUUUUUCUUUCUUCCUUUUUAGAUACAGGGUCUCACUAUGUUGCCCAGGCUGGUCUCCAACUUCUGGGCUCAAACAAUCCUCCCUCCUUGGCCUUCCAAAGGGUUGGAUAUGUUUUAUCUACAGUUUUGUUGUUUUGUUCUGCUACAGGAUAUUUGCAAUUGCCAUUUAUCAUGAAAUUCAUGACAUACCUUCUUCCACUCUCCUUUUUAUCUUUAUUGUUCUGGUUAUAGGACUAGCUUUGCAUCUCUACUCAAUUCUGUAUCAGUAGUAUGCUUUCAUUUUAAAUUUUAAGUUUGUCCAUAUGUAUAUUGACACAGGGUCUUGCUCUGUUGCCCAGACUGGAGUGCAGUGGCAAGAUCAGGGCUCACUGCAGCCUUGACUGCCUAGGCUCAAGUCAUCCUCCCACCUCAGCCUCCAGAAUGGCUGGGACUACAGGCACGCACCACCACACAUGGCUCAUUUUUUUGUAUUGAGACAGGGUUUCUCCAUGUUGCCCAGGCUGGUCUUGAACUACUGGGCUCAAGCAAUCCUCCCACCUUAGCCUCCCAAAGUGUUGGGAUUACAGGCUUGAGCCACCAUGCCUCGCUUCUACACUUAUUUUUAAUUCUAAAAUAAUUUAUAAUAAUAAAUAUUAACAAUUAGAUUUAAUUACUGAUAAAUAUUAAAUGUUAAAUAGGUUUUAUUAAAUAAUUAAAUAAAAAUGAAAAUAAUCAGUAUUUCAAUUUAAUUACUAAUUAUAAUUCACAGUUAUCCUUGUAACUCCUAAUGUCUAUAUAAAAGAUUUUUAUAUUUUUUAAUUCUUAAAAUUUUAUUAUUUAUUUCACACCAGGCCAUCACUGUGAUACAUUUUUUAAAACACAUUAAAUUAUCACCAGAAAAGUGCUGUGAUGGAAAAUAUAAAUUGAAAUACCUUUUCUGGUUAGGAGAGUAAUUCUGUUUUUCUGAUAGAGAAUAGAAGAGUCCUUCAGGCCCCUCCAAACUGUCAUAUUCCGGGCAUCGGGUGUCCCCAUCCUCACUUCAGUCCACAGGCAGGGUCCUCAGUCUUCAGCGCUCCUUCUCUUUCCCCUUUGUCUUGUGUCUCCUUGGGUCUCUUUUCUCCAAGACCUAAACUCCCUGAGGACAGGACUAUUUUUUACAUCUUGAUGUCACUCCUGAGCACUUGCUUUAAUGUGUUGGACACUGGGUCCAUUAAAGAUUGUAUGUGAAAUUAUAAAA